CCAUGAGUUAGGUUGGUGCCAGUACCCUUUCCUCUUGUAUUUAAAUCUGACCUUUAUAUAUAAAGUUUAGAAUAUAAACUUUGUGAGCAGGGUUCUUCUUGUUCACAGAGGUAUUCUAGCACUUAGAAUAGUGUCUGGUAUAUAGCAGCUUGCAGUAAAUACUGUUGAAUGAAUGGUAUGUGAACAGUGCUACCCAGAAGACUGAAUGAAUCUUUAAUGCACAGUUCUUGUUUCAGAGCAAGGAGUUGUAUUCCUAUUCUUUAUGUGAAACUAUGUGGAUACUGUGUAGCUCAGCAGUAGCACCAUGGGUCUGGGCUGCCUCAACCAGUAUCAUUUGCUGGGGUAACUAAGAAGAUUCUUACUGCCCAGCUUACCCAGGAAUAAGGAGAGUCAUAAAUAGAGUCUUCUAAGUCUGUGGGGCUGGGAUUCAAGGUCUCUGUGACUUUAAACUAAAAUCCUGAUGGGGACAGUGCACCCUCACAGUCCUAGGGAGCCCUUUGAACUUAUUCUGCAGAGGCAAAAGUUCUUCUUUUUGGUUGUGUCAUCUUGCAAGGAGUUCCUGGAAUUCCCAGGGCAUCUGUCUACUGGAUUGUGCCCCAGGAAAAGUUGACAGUUUAUUGUCCUGUUUAAGAGCUGGGGAUCUGCAACCAGACCACCUUGUUGAAAUCCUGGCACUGUGAUCUCCCUUAUUUGUGAUCUUCAGCAAAUUACUUAUUUUGUUUCUUAGUUAUCUCAUCUUUAAAAUGAAAAUAGUGUCUAAUUUAUAGUCUCAUUUGUGGAUUAAUAGAGGCAAAGGGCUUAGAACAUGCCUGGCACAUAGUACCAAUGUUCAGUAAAUAUUAACAUGUACAUAUUUGAUACAGAUAAAAUUCAUACUUCUUUUACUCAUUUUCAUUCUAAUAUGCUUUCCUGAGGAAGAUGAGAAGCCACAGAGGUGCAGCUGAUGUUCUGGGAGUUUUACAGAGGCCUACCUGUGCCCAUGGAAGUGUGUUGAGCAUAUGAUAGCACAUAACAUCAGCUUCUAAUGCUGUCAUCCAUCACCAUGUGUCAGGUAGAAAGCAGGUGGAGAACUUUAGCUCUGGAAAGCCCUAAUUAUCCUCAAAGCAGGCUAUGCUUAAUUUGACAGUGUCAUGAUUUUUAAUAUUUGAAAAUUCCAGAAUUGCUGCUCUGGAUGUAAUCCUUUCUUUUUCUUCUCCCUCUUUCCUGCUCUUACUUAUACAGUUAGGUGAAUAUGAUGCUCCACUUCCCCCACAGAUACUCAAAUAGCUCUGACUGCUGAAAUAUUGGUAUCUUACUGUCAGCACAUAACUUGUUGCUGUGUUAUUGACAUUUUCACUGUUUUGAAAUUUUUACUGUUAUCUGGGUUUGAAUCCCAGCUCUCCCAAGCUUCAGUUUUCUUUCAUUUGUCAAAUGAGAUAAAAGUAUCCACUUCAUAGGGUUGUUAUGAGGGUUAAUGAUGAAUACAAAACACUUAACAUAGUACGUGGCAUGUAAUAUUAGUUGUAAAGUUAAUGUAUUCAUUAUCAUCAUUCUGUUUCAAAUCAGCAAUGAAAUACAGACUACACUAAUCCCAUUUCUGCUUGGAAUUGUGAGUCUAAAUGCCAUGUAGCAGUUCCCUGCUUGAAAUACACUGUAAACCUUCCAAUUGCAGUCAAGAUUUUACUACCUUCUAGGGUAUACAGGGAUGGUGGAACAUAGUAAACCUUGAGAUUUGGCUUUCCCGUGUUUGUAUUCUAGCCUUUCUACAAAAAGGUAGUAACCCUAGAUUUCUAUUACAUGCACACCUUGAUGCCUCCUCCAAUAAAACUUCAGUAAUCUAAUUUGUACUCUGUCCUUGAGUUGAAGACAGAAUUAGAAAGUGCAUCCAGUGUGUUUGGUAGCUAAGUUCUGAAAUGGCCUCUAAGAUAAUUACUUUCAUAAUAACCUAUAAAAUUUCAUGUAUAACCACAAGUUAUCAUCCCAGCUUUGUUACGUUUCUUUUUCUUUGACUUGCAAAACAUCCCUCCAUGAGAGAUGGUAUUAUCUCCCAUUUGCAAAUUAGGAAAGCAAGGCUCAGAAAGGUCAAAUAAUUUGCCUAAGGUUGCACACCUGUCUAGUGACACACAGGGUUGAUUCACUCUACAGCUUUUUCCUUUUUUGCUCAGAAUUAGAAAGCUGAAUCCCAAAAUUAGGGUCAAAAUUUUUCCUAUAAAAACUUGUAAAUGAUACAACUAAAAAAAGAGAAUGGAUGCAGUGGCUCAUGCCUGUAAUCCCAACACUUUGGGAGACCAAGACAGGAGAAUCACUUUGAGCCCAGGAGUUCGAGAUCAGCCUAGGCAAUAUAGUGAAACCUUGUGUCUACAAAAAAUUUAAAAAUUAGCCAAAGUUGGUGCAUGUCUGUAGUCCUAGCUGAGGCUGAGGUGGGAGGAUCGUUUAAGCCCAGGAAGCAUAGGUUGCAGUGAGCCAAGAUAGCACCAUUGCACUCCAGCCUGGGCGACAGAGCAAGACCCUAUCUCCAAAAAAAAAAAAAAAAAAAUAAGCAAAAGAAGGUAGACAGGCAGAAAGAAGGUAUGAAGAAAGUUAAGUUAAUAAAUGUGGAACAUAAAAGAUAGGAUGGAAACAAAUUUAUUCAAGUAUCUCUGGUAAACAAUUCAUAUAAGGCCUGUUUGAUGGAGUAUUUUUUUUUUUUUGUAGUGUGAAGUUUUAACUUGGAGACCCAGAAUUCAAACUUGAAACUGUAGAAGAGAGGAUGAAGAGAAUAUUAGCAGUUGAAAGGAAAAUGUAGAAAUAGAAACAUUAUGUAUAUUUAACAGAAAACAAUGAUCAACAUGAAAUGUUGAAGAUAUAUGUUCUAAGUGAUAGCUAUAUGUAGAUAUGGUUCAGAGAAGGCAAAUUGCAUGUAUUGUUUGAUACACGGAGAGAAGAUUCAGGUAUCUGCCCAAACUGGAACUUAUGCUGUAGACAUUUCUUUGUGGUUUAUCUAAAAACCAAAGGGUCUGGCUCUGUACCUACGCUGUAGUGCAGUGGCAUGAUUAUAGUUCACUGCAGCCUCAAACUCCUGGGCUCAAGCAAUCCUCCUGCCUCAGCCUCCUAAGUAGACAGGACUACAGUUGAAUUCUUUUAGAAGAAGGGAAAAACCUCUUGAGAUGUGACUGUUUCCAUCUAUUUUCUGCUUGCCAGGAAAAGAAUACUUGAGAUCCAUUUGUAAGGAAAGAAAAGGAAGCAACAACAUAAUGCCCAGAGUUGGAGCCAAUUAAACCAGGUUUGUACUUUUUCUUUCCAUAAUGUAACAUGUUUAUUCUGGUCUUAAAUCUCUUUUAUUAAUCUCCUGUCUUAUUUCAGCAAAAAUCUAAUAAUUUUAAACCUUGCCAUAGUAGUAUGGAGGAGAUAAAGGUGAAUAAGACAUGCUCUUUUCAAACUAUUUGCAACUAAUGCAAAAGAACAGAAAUCAUAACAGUCUCUGAGACCACAGUGCAAUCAAAUUAGAACUCAGGAUUAAGAAACUCACUCAAAACCGCACAACCAAAUGGAAACUGAACAGCCUGCUCCUGAAUGACUACUGGGUAAAUAACGAAAUGAAGGCAGAAAUAAAGAUGUUCUUUGAAACCAAAUGGUCUUUGAGAACAAAGAUACAACAUACCAGAAUCUCUGGGACACAUUUAAAGCAGUGUAUAGAGGGAAAUUUAUAGCACUAGAUGCCCACAAGAGAAAGCAGGAAAGAUCUAAAAUCAACACUCUAACAUCGAAAUUAAAAGAACUAGAGAAGCAAUAACAAACAAAUUCAAAAGCUAGCAGAAGACAAGAAAUAACUAAGAUCAGAGCAGAACUGAAGGAGGCAGAGACACGAAAAACCCUUCAAAAAAUCAAUGAAUGCAGGAGCUGUUUUUUUGAAAAGAUCAGCAAAAUAGACCGCUAGCCAGACUAAUGAAGAAAAGAGAGAAGAAUCAAAUAGAUGCAAUAAAAAAAAAUGACAUAGGGGAUAUCAAAUGAUUAGCAACUUAACUAUGAAUAUGAAAGACAAAAUUAUAAACAGCUAGAUAGCAAUCUCAUUUUAACAUGGAAAGUUUUGUGAGGUUUGGUAAAUUGCUUGAGGUCAGAAGCUCUUAAAGAGUUAAGUUGGGAUUCAGACUCAUAUCUGCUGACUCCAAACCGUAUUUGCCUUCCAUUAUGUCACAAUGUUCCCUAUUUUAUUUAGGUUUAGUUGUUGUGCAACUGCUGAUUAUUGAAGUAGAGGGUGGAGGACAUAUGUAUUUCAUAUAAGGAAUUUACUUUCAUUUAAGGAAUUUAUUUCAUUUACUUUCUGAUGAAGUAAAAAGGGGGAGAGUAUUCUCUAUUCCUCAAAAGUUUGGAAGAUUAGAGAUGGGAACUAACGUUUAUAAGCACUUACUAUGUGCUAGACACUAUCGUAAGGACUUAACGUGAACUAACUUAUUUAAUUCACGACAGCCAGGUGACAUACUAAUCUUUAAAACAAAGAAAUAAGCAAAUUGUCCGAGAUCACAUAGCUAGUAAGUACCAAAAGCAGAUUCAAAACCGUGUAUUGGGAAAGGUUAGAUAGGGUUUGUAAACCCAUGUCUAUUGACUUACUUUUUUUUUUUUUUUUGAGACGAGUCUCACUCUGUCGCCCAGGCUGGAGUGCGGUGGCGUGAUCUUGGCUCACUGCAACCUCUGCCUUCCGGGUUCGAGUAAUUCUCCUGCCUCAGCCUCCCAAGCAGCUGGGUCUACAGUGAGACUAAUUACAUCCUUCAAUGAAGUACCAUUUUGUGAGAAAGUGAGAAUUCAAUGAUUUAUGAAAAAAUCCAAGAAGGAGAAACAAACAUUUUCUAAUAUGAAAGUAGUAAUGACUACAGCUAUAUAAAUAACAGUAACAAAGAGGGAGAGAAGAACUUUUGUUUUCAAAUAUGAAAUAAAAAUAAGGAUUGGUACCGGCAGAAGCUUGGAAUAAAUGGAGAGUCAGAACCCAAACAGAAUUUCCAUUAGCAUUGAAGAUCUCUGAAAUCAGUUUAUUAUUUGUCCAUGUUUCUGUACUAGAAGUAAACAUUGCUAUCUUCAGAAAUUAAGGAAUGAGAGGCAAGGAAGAAAGGACAUUCAUCUUGGAAAGACCCAAAGCACCUUGAAAUUUGGAAGGAAUGUUUUGCUAGCUGCUAAAACCACCUUUGUCACCAGAAUGAAUGAAGUGCUUCAGAUUUAAAUAAUUUUACUCUCUCAAAUUUGGAAAUGUGGAAUUGAGCAGUUGUGUGAUUUCCUAGAGAGUGGUCUUUGAAAGAUGCAUUGAAAGAAGAAUGUUAAAAGAGCCCAGGAGAUUGAUCAUUCUUAGAAGAGCUGCUGUAACACAUAGGGGAAGUGAAAACUAACAGAUGAAAGUUUUGUCAUGCACUGAAAGAAAAGCAUUGUCUGUGAAGUUCUAUUUUUAAAAAUGUCUGCUUGUAACACCUUUACUGAACAUGUUUGGAAACCUGGUGAAUGCAAGAAUUGCUUUAAACCUAAAAGUUUGCACCAGCUUCCCCCAGACCCUGAGAAGGCACCCAUCACCCAUGGCAAUGUGAAAACUAAUGCCAAUCACAGUAACAACCACCGCAUCAGGAACACGGGCAAUUUCCGGCCUCCUGUGGCUAAAAAACCCACUAUAGCUGUGAAGCCCACUAUGAUAGUGGCAGAUGGGCAAAGUAUAUGUGGUGAGCUUAGCAUCCAAGAACACUGUGAGAACAAACCUGUCAUCAUAGGGUGGAACCGAAACAGAGCUGCCUUGAGUCAGAAACCACUUAACAAUAAUAAUGAAGAUGAUGAAGGAAUUAGCCAUGUUCCUAAGCCUUAUGGCAAUAAUGAUAGUGCAAAGAAGAUGUCAGAUAACAAUAAUGGACUAACUGAAGUGUUAAAGGAGAUAGCAGGCUUGGAUACUGCCCCUCAGAUAAGAGGAAAUGAAACAAACUCCAGAGAAACAUUCUUGGGAAGAAUAAAUGAUUGCUAUAAACGAUCAUUGGAAAGAAAGCUUCCACCAAGUUGCAUGAUAGGUGGGAUAAAGGAAACUCAGGGCAAGCAUGUUAUUCUGAGUGGGAGCACAGAAGUGAUUAGUAAUGAAGGGGGCCGGUUCUGUUACCCAGAGUUUUCCAGUGGCGAGGAGAGUGAAGAGGAUGUACUUUUCAGUAACAUGGAGGAGGAGCACGAGAGUUGGGAUGAGAGUGAUGAAGAGCUGUUGGCCAUGGAGAUUCGCAUGAGAGGGCAACCUCGCUUUGCCAACUUCAGAGCAAACACAUUGUCUCCUGUUCGAUUCUUUGUGGACAAAAAAUGGAAUACCAUCCCCCUGCGAAACAAGUCUCUGCAGAGAAUCUGUGCUGUGGACUAUGAUGACAGCUAUGAUGAAAUCCUGAAUGGUUAUGAGGAAAAUUCUGUGGUCUCUUAUGGACAAGGAAGCAUUCAGAGCAUGGUGUCAUCUGACUCCACAUCACCAGAUUCUUCUUUAACAGAAGAAUCACGUUCUGAGACAGCCAGUAGUUUAUCCCAGAAGAUUUGUAAUGGGGGAUUAUCUCCUGGUAACCCAGGAGAUUCUAAGGACAUGAAGGAAAUUGAGCCCAAUUAUGAAAGUCCCUCUAGUAAUAAUCAGGAUAAAGAUUCAUCACAGGCUUCCAAAAGCUCAAUAAAAGUUCCAGAGACCCACAAAGCAGUCCUUGCUCUCCGAUUAGAAGAGAAAGAUGGCAAGAUUGCUGUACAAACUGAGAAGGAAGAAAGUAAAGCCUCUACAGAUGUUGCUGGGCAAGCAGUAACCAUAAACCUUGUCCCCACAGAAGAGCAAGCAAAACCUUACCGAGUUGUGAACCUGGAACAGCCAUUGUGCAAGCCAUAUACUGUCGUGGAUGUGUCAGCAGCCAUGGCCAGUGAGCACCUCGAGGGCCCUGUUAACAGCCCCAAGACAAAAAGCUCAUCCUCUACUCCAAACUCUCCAGUUACAUCAUCUUCAUUGACACCAGGACAAAUAAGUGCCCAUUUCCAAAAAUCCAGUGCAAUUCGAUACCAAGAAGUAUGGACUUCUAGCACCAGUCCACGACAAAAGAUACCUAAAGUAGAACUAAUUACUAGUGGAACUGGACCAAAUGUUCCUCCAAGGAAAAACUGUCACAAAUCAGCACCUACAUCACCCACAGCUACAAACAUUUCCUCCAAAACCAUCCCUGUUAAGUCACCUAAUUUGUCUGAAAUUAAAUUUAAUAGUUAUAACAAUGCUGGUAUGCCACCUUUUCCAAUUAUCAUUCAUGACGAGCCAACUUAUGCUCGGAGUUCCAAAAAUGCUAUCAAAGUUCCCAUUGUUAUCAAUCCAAAUGCAUAUGACAAUCUAGCUAUCUACAAAAGUUUUCUGGGAACAAGUGGAGAACUCUCAGUGAAGGAAAAAACCACAAGUGUAAUAAGCCAUACUUAUGAAGAAAUAGAAACAGAAAGCAAAGUGCCUGAUAACACCACUAGCAAAACCACUGACUGUCUUCAAACUAAAGGGUUUUCAAACAGCACAGAGCAUAAAAGGGGCUCAGUGGCUCAGAAGGUUCAAGAGUUUAACAACUGUCUCAACAGAGGUCAGUCUUCACCACAGAGAAGCUAUAGUUCCAGCCACAGCUCCCCAGCAAAGAUCCAGAGAGCCACUCAAGAGCCUGUGGCCAAAAUAGAAGGCACUCAGGAGUCUCAGAUGGUGGGCAGCAGCAGCACCAGAGAGAAAGCAAGCACAGUGCUUUCUCAGAUUGUGGCUUCAAUCCAACCCCCACAGUCUCCUCCAGAAACACCUCAAUCUGGCCCUAAAGCUUGCAGUGUGGAAGAGCUUUAUGCCAUUCCUCCAGAUGCUGAUGUUGCUAAGAGCACACCUAAGAGUACGCCAGUCCGGCCCAAAUCUCUCUUUACAUCUCAGCCUAGUGGUGAGGCUGAAGCACCUCAGACCACAGACAGUCCUACCACCAAAGUACAGAAAGACCCAUCCAUAAAGCCAGUCACCCCCUCUCCCUCCAAAUUAGUGACUAGCCCCCAAAGUGAGCCACCAGCUCCCUUUCCCCCGCCACGCUCUACUUCUUCUCCUUACCAUGCAGGUAACCUUUUGCAGAGGCAUUUCACCAACUGGACCAAGCCAACCAGCCCUACCAGGUCAACAGAAGCUGAAUCAGUUUUGCACUCUGAAGGCAGCAGGCGGGCAGCUGAUGCAAAACCUAAGCGCUGGAUAUCAUUUAAAAGCUUCUUCCGCCGUCGGAAAACAGAUGAGGAGGAUGACAAAGAGAAAGAGCGAGAGAAAGGGAAACUGGUGGGCCUGGAUGGCACAGUCAUUCACAUGCUGCCUCCUCCUCCAGUUCAGCGCCAUCACUGGUUCACAGAGGCGAAAGGAGAGUCCAGUGAGAAACCAGCCAUUGUCUUCAUGUACAGGUGCGACCCUGCUCAAGGCCAGCUCAGUGUGGAUCAGAGCAAGGCUAGGACAGACCAGGCAGCAGUCAUGGAGAAGGGUAGAGCAGAGAAUGCAUUACUACAGGACUCAGAGAAGAAGAGGAGUCAUUCUUCUCCAUCACAGAUUCCUAAAAAGAUUCUCAGUCACAUGACCCAUGAAGUAACAGAGGAUUUUUCUCCUCGGGAUCCAAGAACUGUUGUUGGGAAGCAAGAUGGCAGGGGCUGCACUUCAGUCACAACAGCAUUGUCCCUACCUGAACUGGAAAGGGAAGAUGGAAAAGAAGACAUUUCAGAUCCUAUGGACCCGAACCCUUGUAGUGCAACAUACAGCAACUUAGGGCAAUCUAGAGCAGCCAUGAUACCUCCCAAGCAGCCACGACAGCCCAAGGGAGCUGUGGACGAUGCCAUCGCCUUUGGAGGGAAAACAGACCAAGAAGCACCCAAUGCUUCCCAACCUACACCACCCCCACUGCCAAAGAAGAUGAUCAUAAGAGCCAAUACAGAGCCAAUCUCCAAGGACCUCCAAAAAUCCAUGGAAAGUAGUCUUUGUGUCAUGGCUAAUCCCACCUAUGAUAUCGACCCCAACUGGGAUGCCAGCAGUGCUGGUUCUUCCAUCAGCUAUGAACUCAAAGGACUGGACAUUGAGUCUUAUGACUCCUUGGAAAGGCCUUUGCGCAAGGAGAGACCUGUCCCCUCAGCAGCAAACAGCAUUUCCAGCUUAACCACUCUCAGUAUUAAGGAUAGAUUUUCCAACAGCAUGGAAUCCCUCUCCAGCCGGCGUGGGCCCUCUUGCAGACAGGGCCGAGGCAUCCAGAAGCCGCAGAGACAAGCACUUUAUCGAGGACUUGAGAAUCGGGAGGAAGUAGUGGGUAAAAUCCGAAGCCUUCAUACAGAUGCCUUGAAGAAACUGGCUGUUAAAUGCGAAGACCUUUUCAUGGCUGGGCAGAAAGACCAGCUCCGUUUUGGAGUGGACAGCUGGUCAGACUUCAGGCUAACCAGUGACAAACCAUGUUGUGAGGCAGGUGAUGCGGUUUACUAUACUGCUUCAUAUGCAAAAGAUCCACUUAAUAACUAUGCAGUCAAGAUCUGUAAGAGCAAAGCUAAAGAAUCUCAGCAGUAUUAUCACAGCUUGGCUGUCCGGCAGAGUCUGGCUGUCCAUUUUAACAUUCAGCAGGACUGUGGUCAUUUCCUUGCUGAAGUCCCUAACCGUCUGCUUCCCUGGGAGGAUCCAGAUGACCCUGAAAAGGAUGAGGAUGACAUGGAAGAGACUGAAGAAGACGCCAAAGGAGAAACGGAUGGGAAAAACCCAAAGCCCUGUUCUGAAGCAGCAUCAUCCCAGAAAGAGAAUCAGGGAGUCAUGAGCAAGAAGCAGAGGAGCCACGUUGUGGUCAUCACCAGGGAGGUUCCAUGUCUUACUGUGGCUGAUUUUGUGCGAGACUCUCUGGCCCAGCAUGGGAAAAGCCCUGAUUUGUAUGAGAGGCAGGUGUGUCUGCUGCUCUUACAGCUAUGCUCUGGUCUUGAGCACCUCAAACCCUACCAUGUCACUCACUGCGAUCUACGCCUAGAGAACCUGCUACUUGUCCACUACCAGCCUGGGGGGACUGCCCAAGGCUUUGGGCCUGCAGAGCCCAGCCCCACCUCAUCUUAUCCCACUAGGCUUAUAGUGAGCAACUUCUCUCAGGCCAAGCAGAAGAGCCAUCUGGUGGACCCCGAGAUCCUCCGGGACCAGUCUCGCCUUGCCCCAGAGAUCAUAACAGCUACCCAGUAUAAAAAGUGUGAUGAGUUCCAGACAGGCAUCCUCAUCUAUGAGAUGCUGCACCUACCCAACCCCUUUGAUGAGAACCCAGAGCUGAAGGAGAGGGAAUACACACGAGCAGACCUGCCUCGCAUCCCAUUCCGCUCCCCCUACUCCCGGGGUCUGCAGCAGCUGGCCAGCUGCCUCCUGAAUCCCAACCCUUCUGAGCGGAUCCUCAUUUCAGACGCCAAAGGCAUCCUCCAGUGUCUGCUCUGGGGCCCCCGCGAAGAUCUCUUCCAGACUUUCACCGCCUGCCCUAGCCUAGUACAGAGGAACACCCUGCUCCAAAACUGGCUAGACAUCAAGCGAACACUGCUCAUGAUCAAGUUUGCUGAGAAGUCCCUGGACAGGGAAGGUGGAAUCAGCCUUGAGGACUGGCUUUGUGCUCAGUAUUUGGCUUUUGCCACUACAGACUCCCUCAGUUGUAUUGUGAAAAUUCUGCAGCACCGUUAAUGUGUACCUGGAUGAUGCUUUUACUACAUCUUCACCUUCUUCAUGUCACCCAUGCACUUCCCCUCCCUAGUGCUCACUCCAAAUUCAAGGAAAGAAGAAAGGCAAACCUCUAUCCCUGUCCGUGAACAAGUGGGUCUAUUCAGAAAGGUUAUCCACUGCCCCAGAUUGAAUGAGAAGCUGAGUCUGUCUUAACUUUACAGAAAUUCAGCUGCACAAACUUGCAGUUGCCUUCCCUUGAAACACCUUCUAUCCUAAUAGUCCCAUAAAUGCAGGUAAAAAUGAAAAUCCAUAUUCUUGAAGGGACAGCUUCUUUGGUAUGAACUCAGCCAGUGAGCUGUGUCCAUUUCCUCCAUAAUUCUGGAUAUCACCUAUCUUUUUAGCACCAAGUAUUUAUUCUCACUAGCAGUAGACAGACUUAACCAGUCUCUACCACGACCCAGUAGACUCUGACAACAGACUCUUCCUUUAAGGUGUCAACAACUGACUUACUAGGCAGGACUGCCAUCCUUAGCAUCAGCCCAGUUUUGGUUACCAGGGACUAUAUCUUUUGUUCCAGGAGAGAGUAGAAAGAAAAGGAGAGAUCCCAUCCUUGGGUCAUAGACCCAUUUUCAUUGCCAUUAUCUGUAAGUAUGUGCACUGCAUGGAGGACAGCCCUAAUAGUCUCCCCUCUGCUGCCACUGCCUGAUUCUCCACUCUGUCCCCACUUGCCAGUGAAGUUUGGAUUUAUCAGCCACUUGUGGCCCAUUACAGAGCUGACCCAAGGUGGUGUCACCAAUGCCUCAGCAGGGUGGAGUGCAGUUCAGAGCUUAUAAAUAGCUGGCAGGGCAUGAGGAGAUGAUUUUCUUGCAUGUGCAAUUCUCUAGGGGCCAUCAGGAAACAGAGUUUAAAGUACCCUUUGAUUACUGUCAGAACUGUCAGCAUUUGCAGUUUUCCCCGAGCAGUAAUUGGCCAGCUCCCUUCUAUCAGUAGCCAGUGUUAACUAGUUUACCAAAUGCUGUAAACAAUUGCCCUGAAUGAAAUAGCUGUCAGUGGAGCUCUAAGAUCUCCUUUAGAGGGCACAGUGAGGUGGGCUGUUGGGAUGGCCGUAGGCAGGGGAGAGGAAGAAGGCCACUGAUGAGACUGCUGACCUCCUCAGAAGGUUGACCUCUUCUAGAGAGACUGCCUCCCAGUGUUUAAGUGGCUCAUUGCUCCUUCUGACUCUGUAAAAUGGCUCUGGAGGACAGCUCACAGGAAUUCUGAUUGCUGAGGUGGGUGAUUGAGAGCUGUUCACCAUGUGUGCAGCCUGUGCUCCCCUUCUAUGGAUAUGUGUGCAAUUUUUGUAUGUAUUUUUUUAGCUGUAUAUUACAGUGUUUAUGUUGCAACUUCACCUGAAGCGAGUCUACAGAAACCCUCCCCCUUCUUCCCUUGGCACAUAUUUGCGCUAAGAGAUGAGCGUUCCUUCCACUGGGGUUGUGUGUGUGUGUGUGUGUGUGUGUGUGUGUGUGUGUGUGUGUGUAUGUAUACACAUGUUCACCUGUGCUUGUUUUAUUCAAAACUGUGAGUAUGUGUUUACUUUGACCUUGAAAUCCCAAGAGUCACUCGAACAAUGUGUGUGUACACUUGUGUGCCCAUGUGUGCGUGCACACGCAUGCUGGAAGUAGAGGCCAGGCCUCUAGAAAAGCAACCUGUGGCAGGGUUGACAGACAUGUUCUCUGUGCCUAGUGAGUGAGUGAGCCCUGAGGCCCCUCAUCUACCAGUGCAGAGUUUCCUUAAAGCCAAGACUGACUGUGCAGUAUUACUUACAUAGCACAUUAGUGGCCUUGGAAAUUUCUAAACUUUUAACAUUUUUAACAGCUUUUCAUGUGAUUCAUGUAUAACAAAGAGGAUCAGGAAAGGAAAAUAAUGUAUUUUAUUGUGCUCUUAUUACUUUUUUAAGUGAUUGUAAUAUGUGAGGCUCUAUUUGGAGAAUGUCCCUUAUCCCCUGGCCAGCAAUAUAGGACUCACAGGAAAGAAGGCUGGUUAGCCCACAAAGAGUCUUGCCUCCUCUAGCCAGAGUGCAGGGCUCUGCUCCUAGGAAUGGCCAUGGAGUGGGCAUGCUGCUGCAGGCCAGCAGUCUGCUCUUGGUGUCCUGUGGCAUGGCCGCGCCUUGCCUUGAAGGUUGGUGUUUGGUUCAUCUUAGCAUAGAACAUGUGCACAUAACUCCUUGCCUGAUUAUGCACUGAAGGGCAGCACACAGACCACUGACCAUGUCAGCCAGCACAUUCCCUUAACCUCCCCCACCUCCCAUCUUGCAAUGUCUUGCAUAUUGAGAUAUACCUUCUCAAUGUCAUGUUCGUGGUGCCUUGCCCAUGUAAAUUUCAAUGUUGACUAUUUAAUGAGGUUACAUAUUUAAUGCUGAAUGUUUCCUGGUCCCUCUAUUUGUUAUGUCUCUACUUAUCUUUUUUUUUCUUUCUCUUUUUCUGUUAUGAUUUGGAUCCAGUCUUCACUUUAACUCUAUGGUAUAAUAAGCAUGGACACCUCCACUACCAUUAUCUUACAGCACUGGUAAACCAAGCACCUCUUCAUAUCAGAUGUUUUUAGUACUGUUUUUAUAUUCAGAUUUGUUAAGGGCAAAAGAUGAAUGCAAACUAGCCAGAGAAAAGCCUCAGGCUUCCCAGAGACAGGUGGCUAGAUUAAUUUUUCUCUGGGUGAUGGCCAAAGAAUGUGAGAUAGAGAGGGAAGGGGGUGUUACAGGUUAGAGCAGAAUAGAGAAAGAAACUAUAUUUCUAGGCAAAAAGUACUACAUGAGUUGGUCUUCAGAAUAUUUUUCCAAAAAAAUGAAAUUCAGUCAGUUUAACAUUAUCACAAAUAUUUUUCAUUUUAAUUGUGGUAGGACCUUUGAAUUUGUUCAUCAACUGGAAAGAAAUCCUACCCUCUGUAGACACAUACACACACAUUUAUAUAUCUAUGUGUUUGAAUUGUGACUAGUAUAGCACUUUACAUUUUCUCAAGUAACAGGAAGUUAUUGCCUUCAAUAUUGAUUGGAAAUUGUUUUCUAUUGAAGUCUAUACUGUAGAGUUUUCCAUUUAUAUUGAGAGUUUGAACAAUUAAGCUCCUAUUGGAACUUUUCCUUAAGCCACAUGAGCAUGAACAAUCUCUGUGACACUUGGGUGCUAGAGAAACACAACAGUGGCUAAAGUAGCCAAGAGCAAGACUGAAUGUAUAGCAGAGUGCCUUGUUAGAGUGGUAACCUAGUCUUGGAAGCAAUUCAGUGGAUGUUUCAUAAAGAGGACUAGAACUUCAAGAAGCCUCCUGUGCUGGCUGAGGUGAGCCCUUUUGGUAUAUGUACACUACUGGGUUGCCUAGAAGCCAAUUCAUGAAGAAUAACAGCAGGAUGAGAAAAAGAGUCACUGUAACCUGUGGAACAACAACGUAAGAAUCACCAACCCCUAGGCUGAGCUAGAACUGGAAGCCAGGAAUAUGGCAAUGAGUUUCAAGAUUUGCCCUCAGAAGAUGAACUGGGUGAGGUAUGGGUUGAGGUGAGGGCACAAGCACUCAUCCUACCUACCCUGCUGCUGUUGAGGAGCUAGAAGUAAAACAUAUUGGUUAGGAUUUUAACAGUUGGAGUAGCCUCCCAUUAUCAGAUUAAGUGGGGGUCACUUUUGCUUCCAAACUCAGAAUAAGUUUGUAAACAUGGGAAAGUCUAAGCCAAGAGAUCUAAAGCUCUAGAAAUAUUAAUGACAUUUCUGGGAGUAAAACUACUAAAAAUUAUAUCUUAAAAGUUUCUAGUAGUAUGAAGUUCCCAGGCCAGGCGCAGUGGCUCACGCCUGUAAUCCCAACACUUUAGGAGGGCGAGGUGGGCAGAUCACCUGAGGUCAGGAGUUUGAGACCAGCCUGGCCAACAUGGUGAAACUCCAUCUCUACUAAAAAUACAAAAAUUAGCCGGGCAUGAUGGCAGGCACCUGUAAUCUAAGCUACUCGGGAGGCUGAGGCAAGAGAAUCUCUUGAACCCAGGAGGCAAAGGUUGCAGUGAGCCAAGAUCACGCCAUCGCACUCCAGCCUGGGAGAUUGAGCAACUUCGUCUCAAAAAAAAGUUUCCAGGAAAGAUCUUUGGGUCCUACUAAGCGUCUCAAUUUUGAGUUAUGAAUACUUUGGUUCAGGGAAGUAACCUGACAUUUGGUUUUGCUGGAAUUAGGGUUUUCGCUAGAUUUGACUGCAAUUAGGAUUUCUUCUAGAUUUUACCAGCAGUGAUCUGAAAAAGUACAGGCUAGUCACAGAAAUAGAGAUGGAUUUAGGAUACUACACUAUAUUUCAAAUGAUUCUAGAUGUGUAAAUAUAGUAUGAACAUUCUUGGAGAGGGGUGAGACAAACUGGACUUGCUGGGCCAACCCUGGCAUGUUUUUCAUUCUCCUCACUAGUUGACAAGGAUUGAAAAUUCCGCUCCAGCCUAAUGAGUGAACAGGAUGGCUGCCCACAAAACCAAGUUAUUAGCUUUAUGUCAUCGAAGCUCAUAUUCUCAAAGGCCCAAAGUGCUGUGCCGAGACAAAUCCAAGUGCUGCUCUUGCUGAAGUGCGCACUGAAGUCCAGCUGUCCGUGCUUACAGCAGUGCCAAAAGUGGGGAUUCCAUGGACCAAAAACGGUGCCAUAAGGGAAGCCAGAAGAGUUGCAGUGCAAGAUCCUGGGAGAGAUUAUACCAAAGAAAUCAAGCCUUUUUAUCCUGAUGCUUCUAAGAUGAUGAGGGUGAGCUGUGACAGAUGCUGUGGGAGGGGAGUUCACAUACAUUCCAUGUCAAGGCAUUUAGCUGAUAAAUCCAUCCUCAGAAAAGCACCUUUUUAAAAAGAAGUCCAUUUUGUAUAUUAGAAGAUGAUGAUGAUGAUGAAGAUGAAGAAAGCCCUGGCAGAUACAAAGUUCCUCAGUAUUUAAGGAGAAGGAUCUCUUCCAUGUCCCCUUGACAUGACUGUGGCUAUUGCCCAAACCUCAGCUUGAGAACAUCAUAUAAUACUGAGAGCGGAAGAUUUUUUUAAAGAGAUAUGGUAGUUUAAAUAGGUUUGUUUAAAGAACUCUUGGGAAAUUUCUUAACAAAUUGUAAUUGUUUUUAUAAACCUUCCUACAGAGUUGUGUACCAUUCAUCAUCACCAUCAUUUAAUAUCUGUAAGUGCCCAGAAGGUACAAGGUGCUAUACAGCCGUUAAACACCCCCUCCCUGCAACUGUUUAAAAUUAGAAUAGAUUUUUGCAUCAACCACUGCUAGAAGCUUUCCCCACCUAGGUGGGCUGCAAGGGCCUGCAUUCCCAACAUCCCAUUACAUGUUUCCCACUCCAGAAAGUCUCUGGGUUUAUUCCAGCUUUUUAUCUUGACGUGUCCCAUUCACCCCCAUGGUUUGGUUUGGUUUGGUUUUGUUUUUUAAAUCAAGAAAGUUUCAGGGAAUCAAAAGAGGUCGGACAUUUUUUAACCUAGCAGAAGUACAGAGUCAUAUAUUUUGCUACGAAUAUUGUUGUAGUACAGAAAACCCACUUUGCCCGUUAGUGUGUGGAUAGUAUGUGUGUGUCCGCACUCAUGAUAACUUGAAUGUUGAACCAGACAUAGGGUUCAUUUUUGAAAGGUUAAACCACACUGUUUCAGGAACUUGCUCCAAAUACUACUUGGUUAUCCCUUCCUUUACCAGUUAGAACUAAAGAGUGUGAUGUAUGAACACACUGGGUUGGGAUUUUCUGUUGAGGAUAUGCAGGGCAUUUUGGCAUGAGGCAAAUACAGAAGCAAGAUUUCAUUCUACUUGGUGAUUUGAAUCAUGACAGUCCUCAUUCCAAUCUCUCUUUAAUUCUCUCUGGCCCUGCCCACACUCUGUAUUUGAAAAUCUUGUUUUUGCUCUUUCCGGAGCUUCACCCCUCUACUUACAUAUUGUAAAGUUGUAUAAAUCUAUCAUUGAAAGGUCCUCUCUGCCAGCAGUGGUGCCACCCUUUGGUUUGCUGUGGUACUUUGCUGUGUACUCCGUGGCAUCAUGUUACUGUGUAAAUAAAUUCAUUUUAAUACACACUAAAAAA